AGACAGCUGUUCACUCUUGUUGUCCAGGCUGGAGGGCAGUGACAUGAUUUCGGCUCACUGCAACCUCUGCCUCUCAGGUUCAAGUGAUUCUCCUGCCUCAACCUCCUGAGUAGCUGGGAUUACAGGCAUGCGCCACCAAGCCCAGCUAAUUUUUUUUUGUAUUUUUAGUAGAGAUGGGGUUUCACCAUGUUGGCCAGGCUGGUCUCGAACUCCUGACCUCAGGUGAUCCGCCUGCCUUGGCCUUCCAAAGUACUGAGAUUGCAGGCAUGAGCCACCCGCCCAGCCAAUAAUAGAAUCUUUUUUUUAAGUUUAAUGAAGGAUAGACGAGAUGAAGGACAGAUUAAUAGCCAAUUUCACUCUCUAUGAAUAAUUAACUGUCAAACUUCAGUUUAUGCCAGUAGGAACCUGGGCGUUAAAGAGGUUUAACUGGGUUUUGACAAACCUGGAUUUGGAUCUGAGCUCUGCUAUGUUAGAGCUAUAGAAGCCUUUGUAUGUUAGAACUAAGUUGUAGCUACAUAAAUUCAAGUCAUUUACUUGUGCCUCAGUCUCUCCUUUUGUAAAAAUAAGGGCAAUAUUUAUCUCAUAAAGAUGUUGGGGAUCAAAGGAAAUAGAAAGUGUUCAUCUCAAAAGCUAAGUAUGUAGUUAUUCAGCAGAUGUUAAUUCUACUCACCCAUUUGUACUCACCAAUUCUACUAAUUCAGUCUUUUAAAUCUCUUGUUUUAUCUCUUCCCUUUGUCCCUGAUAUUACCACUGCUUUUGUUUAGCAACUCAUCUCUUCUGCUACUAUUCUUACUUUCUGUUUCAUCUAUCUUCUAUAUUGAGCCACAGGAUGUUUUCAGUACAGAAAUCUAAGUGUUCAGAUUUUAUUAACUGAAAUGCUGUGCUUUAUACUUCCCGGUUUUGCUGAUCCUGAAAUUUUAGAUGGGUGGACUUAAUGAAUAAGUCUCAUAUAAUUUCGUGAUAUAUUCCAAGCAGUGUACUUAAUUAAGCACAUUCAAAAUGAAGUUGUUUACCAUAGAAUAAAUGUCUGUUGUGAUAGGCAGAGUAGAAUUGAGGAUGUGGUAAACACAGGCCAGGGCAGAUUCAGAAGUAGUAGUAAUUUGCCUUUUUAAAAAAAUGAUAACACUUUUUUAUUAAAUUCUAAUUCUGUUAUGUGUGUCACUACUCUUAGUUCCUAAUUUGGUAUUAAUAGGAAAUAUGAAUUAUUAUAUACUUAAUAAAAUUUAGAAUUCUGUUAAAAUGCAUGAUCUCUAUCAAAUUUCCUAUGCAUCUACAUGCAAUAAUGAACUCUUGGUUAUUAAUUUUUUUUUUCUUUUUGAGACGGAGUAUCGCUCUGUCACCCAGGCUGGAGUGCAGUGGCACAGUCUCGGCUCACUGCAACCUCCGCCUCCUGGGUUUAAGCCAUUCUUCUGCCUCAGCCUCCUGAGUAGCUGGGACUAUAGGCGCGCGCCACCACGCCUGACUAAUUUUUGUAUUUUUAGUAGAGACGGGGUUUCACCAUAUUGGCCAGUCUGGUCUCAAACUCCUGACCUCGUGAUCCGCCUGCCUUGGCCUCCCAAAGUGCUGGGAUUACAGGCGUGAACCACCGCGCCCGGCCAUUAAUUUUUCUUCUUGAACUUAUUAUUUUAUUGAUAAUCUUCAUUGUUCCUGCUUGUAUCCUGUAAGGGAGAAAUGAGGUGUUCUUUAAUUCUGUUUUUUUUAAAUUAUAAAUAAGUAAAGAAAUAUUAAAAACUAUGACGAGCUUUAUGGAUAAAUUGAAAAUCCCAGAGGAGGCUUUUUUCUCCUUUUUUUAUUCCAGCAUAAUUAAAAUAUUUUUCUUUGCAUCUGUAAAUAUGUUUCUUUAGCCUUUUGGAAACAAUUUUACUAUUUUAAUCUGUAUCUGAUGCUCUAGACAUUCGAAUCUGUGUUUGAAAAUCCAUCAUCAUUAAAUUACAAAGUGAUUCCUAUUUUAAAAGGUAGGAUCCUUCAGUGUCUGUUAGAUGCAAGUUACCGUGGCAACCUAAUAGCAAACUGCAAAUCCCAGGUCAUGCUCAGCAAAUAAAAAACAUUCUCAGCAAAUAAAAAACAUCGUCAUCACGUAGUGUUUGGGUGUACUGUCUUCUAUAUAGAAUCUCACAUUCCUUGUGAGAAGCGUAUCACAUUUUCCCUAGUGCGUUAUCCAUUAGCUUAUGUCUGAGUGCUUGCUAACUGCAUGAUCAUGUGUUAGGCAUUAAUAAAAACAGUUUCUAAAAGGGCAUUAAAUGUUGGGGACACCAAAAAGUAAUGCUUUCUGUUUGCUCUUCUAUAAUAAAUAAAUUACUGCUCAGUAACUGAGAAGGGAAUAGAGGGUGGUUAGCAGAGAAGAAAGUGUUGGAAAAAUAAUGGCCUGGUAGUAUCUCAGGGAAUUUAAAUUAAUAAUAAACUGAAACCGAUCUAUGUUGAUUCUUAUUAAAUAUUUUGAAAAAUAUUUUUGAUUUUAAUAACAGUUUCAAAACAUUAAAUAAUUUGUAAAAAUGAAGCUGAAUAUUAUGUAGCUGUAACUGUAAUGGUAAUAUUGUCUUAAAAGGCAUUUGUUUAGGUUAAAUAUCCUUCUUUGGAUGGUAAGUAAUGUACCCUUUAAAUGGUAUUCGACUUCAUAAUAUAUAAGGUUCUUCAUUGACUUCAGGAUAGGAUAAAGUCCCAGUUAUUUUCCAUGGUUUACAUAACAAUUCAACUCUAAUGUGCAUGUGAAUCACCUUAAGUCUUGUUAAAGUGAAGAUUCUGAUUCACUUGCUCUAGGGUGGGGCCUGAGAUUCUGGAUAUCUGAUAGGUGGAUAUCUUCCCAGGAGAUGUAGAUCUUGCUUGCCAGUCCUUGGACCACACUUUAAAUAUGAGGAGUCUACAAGUCCUUUUGUGGUCUGUUUCUUCCCUAAUGCUCUAACUUUAUUGCUUCCUAGCUGUGCCUUAUAAUUUAUGACACUGUAUCAUGGACUUGCUUUUAGUAUCCCCCUGUAGCUGCACUUUGCAAAAUGUGGUGCAGGAAUCCAUGAGACUCUUGCAAGGGAUCUACAAGGCCAAAACUGUUUUAAUGAUAAUAGUAAGAUGUUAUUUGCCCUUUUCACUCUCAUUCACUUAUGAGUGUACAGUGGAGUUUUCCAGAGGUUACAUGGCUUGUGAGAUGUCAUUGCUGUGACUGAUGGAAUAUAUACUGUGUGUCCCUUGUUUUAAAAGUUGCUCAGUUUUGGCCAGCCGUGAUGACUCACACCUAUAAUCCCAGCACUUUGGGAGGCCGAGGUGGGCAGAUCACUUGAGGUCAGAAGUUCGAGAUCAGCCUGGCCAACAUGGCAAAACCCCAUGUCUACUAAAAAUAAAAAAUUAGCUGGGCAUGGUGGCACGCACCUUAAUCCCAGCUACGUGGGAGGCUGAGGCAAGAGAAUCGCUUGAACCCAGGAGGUGGAGGUUGCAGUGAGCUGAGAUUGUGCCACUGCACUCUAGCCUGGGAGACAGAGCAAGACUCCAUCUCAAAAAAAAAAAAAAAAGAAAGAAAAAGAAAAAAAGUUGUUUAGUUUUAAUUUCUAAUAUAAUAAAUAUUGAUAGACAUAAGCAAAAGCUCUUUGAAGUCCUUUGUAAAAGAGAUUACAACCUUUGAGAACUGCUUCCCUCCAUAUUGGACUGCGGACAAAGAGACUCAGAUCUGGAACUUGGAGCUAUUUCCUUAGCCACAGCAACUGCUAGGCUAGGGUGGCAGUUUCAGUUUCCCAUAUGGUCUCCAGUGACACUGCAGUGGGAGUGGUCUUCUCACCUCUGGGCAAUGGGAAAAGUCCCGACUUUCCACUAGGCCUCCUUUGAUACUAGCCAACUAGGAGAAGGAGUAAGUAACACCGUAUUACUUCCUGUAUGGGUGGAAAUCUAGGCUCUCUAGGUGGUCUCCGCUGACACCAUUAUCAUGGCUCCCUACUUGUCUACAUAGCCUUUGACUCUACCCCAGUUAGGGUGUUGAGAUGCCACCUUGUAGCCUCACUAGGGUGGAAGUCCAGACUACCCACUUGGAUUUUGCUUGCAUGGGUAGGGGAGCCAGGUAUAUACAUGGUAUGGAGAGGGUUGCUGUGGUCUAAUAUUUGGGGGAUUUCAGUACAUUGAGCCUAGAACUGUUCCUCAUAUUCUUAUAUCUUAGAAAUUUUUGAUUAUGUUAGAGAUUUUUGUCUCCUUUUAGCAAACAAUUAAAUUAGAUACCUAUCAUUUUAGGUCUUAAAUGUACUCUAAAGGAAAAAAUGAAAGCAGCAGUCAAAGAGGUCAUAAAGUUUAAUUUUAAUCAUAAACUAUCAGCUUUGACUGGAGAUCCAGUAUUCAUAUGUUUAGCAAAAUCAUGUGUAAUUUAAAAGAUGUUAAUUUUCUAGGUUUAAAUUUUGUAGUAUAUUGGCAAAAAAUAGACAAUCAACCUGGACUUUUUUUUUAGGGAAGAGUUAAAGGAAACCACUGGUGCUAAGCAAUGUGCUUCAAAAUAUGAUUCUUUGGGAAAACAACUUAAAAAUUAAAAGUUUUAUCUGAUUACUUUAUAACUUGUGAAAAUUGUGCAUUGCUUUGGAAUAAUUUCAGGAGUCACCAUGCCAUCUCUAUGAAUAGAUUUAGAAAACUAGAAACCACAAUUUCACAAAAUCUUUUACCUUUUGUGAGUUUAGUAGUCACAACAUUUAGGUAGGCUUAUACUGAUAAAAUCUUGGCUAUGAAUACCUCUGAAGUAAAAUCAACUAGUAUAGAAUAUGCAGAUGUUAAAGCAAUACAAACUUACUAUCUUACGCUUCUGUGGAUUAGAAGUCCAACACAGAUCUCACUGGGCUAAAAUCCAGAUGUCAGUAGGGCUAUGUUCUGUUUUAGGGCCUCUAGGGGAAAAUCUAUUUCCUUGCCUUUUCCAGCAUUUUUUGACUCAUGUCCCUCUUCCUUAGUGCAAGAUGCAAGACUAAUUUACUUUAAUUUUUAAGGUAAAAAUGGAUGGACAUAGUACCUAAAGUUUAAUUAGCCUUGUUAGAUUUAUUUUGUUGAGUUUAAUAUAUAUGGAACUUGAUUUACCUCAUUGUUACUAUAAAUAUUUGUUCAGACCUGAUGGCCAAAAGAAAGGAAGAAAAUUUUUCCUCUCCUAAAAAUGCCAAAAGGCCAAGACAAGAAGAAUUGGAGGAUUUUGAUAAAGAUGGUGACGAAGACGAAUGUAAAGGUACUACUUUGACUGCAGCAGAAGUUGGAAUAAUUGAGAGUAUUCACCUAAAAAACUUCAUGUGUCAUUCAAUGCUUGGACCUUUUAAGUUUGGUUCUAAUGUCAACUUUGUUGUUGGCAACAAUGGAAGUGGGAAGAGUGCAGUACUCACAGCUCUCAUAGUCGGUCUUGGUGGAAGAGCAGUUGCUACUAAUAGAGGAUCCUCUUUAAAAGGUUUUGUGAAAGAUGGACAGAACUCUGCAGAUAUCUCAAUAACAUUGAGGAACAGAGGAGAUGAUGCCUUUAAAGCCAGUGUGUAUGGUAACUCUAUACUUAUACAGCAACACAUCAGCAUAGAUGGAAGUCGAUCUUAUAAACUUAAAAGUGCAACAGGCUCCGUGGUUUCCACGAGGAAAGAAGAGCUGAUUGCAAUUCUUGAUCAUUUUAACAUCCAGGUGGAUAAUCCAGUUUCUGUUUUAACACAAGAAAUGAGCAAGCAGUUCUUACAGUCUAAAAAUGAAGGAGACAAAUACAAAUUCUUCAUGAAAGCAACGCAACUUGAACAGAUGAAGGAAGAUUAUUCAUACAUUAUGGAAACGAAAGAAAGAACAAAGGAGCAGAUACAUCAAGGAGAAGAGCGGCUUACUGAACUAAAGCGCCAGUGUGUAGAGAAAGAGGAACGUUUUCAAAGUAUUGCUGGUUUAAGUACAAUGAAGACUAAUUUAGAGUCCUUGAAACAUGAAAUGGCUUGGGCAGUGGUCAAUGAAAUUGAAAAACAAUUGAAUGCCAUCAGAGAUAAUAUCAAAAUUGGAGAAGAUCGUGCUGCUAGACUUGACAGGAAAAUGGAAGAACAGCAGGUCAGACUUAAUGAGGCAGAACAAAAGUACAAGGAUAUUCAAGACAAACUAGAAAAGAUUAGUGAAGAGACAAAUGCACGAGCACCAGAAUGUAUGGCAUUGAAAGCAGAUGUUGUUGCUAAGAAAAGGGCCUAUAAUGAAGCUGAGGUUUUAUAUAACCGAUCCUUAAACGAAUAUAAAGCAUUAAAGAAAGAUGAUGAGCAGCUUUGUAAACGAAUUGAAGAGCUGAAAAAAAGUACUGACCAAUCUUUGGAACCUGAACGGUUGGAAAGACAAAAAAAAAUAUCUUGGUUAAAAGAGAGAGUAAAGGCCUUUCAAAAUCAAGAAAAUUCAGUCAAUCAAGAGAUCGAACAGUUUCAGCAAGCCAUAGAAAAGGACAAAGAAGAACAUGGCAAAAUUAAGAGAGAAGAAUUAGAUGUGAAGCAUGCACUGAGCUACAAUCAGAGGCAACUGAAAGAAUUGAAAGAUAGUAAAACUGAUCGACUCAAAAGAUUUGGCCCUAAUGUUCCAGCUCUUCUUGAAGCCAUAGAUGAUGCUUAUAGACAAGGACAUUUUACCUAUAAACCUGUAGGCCCUUUAGGAGCUUGCAUUCAUCUUCGGGACCCAGAACUUGCUUUGGCUAUUGAAUCUUGCUUAAAAGGGCUUCUGCAGGCCUAUUGUUGCCAUAAUCAUGCUGAUGAAAGGGUCCUUCAGGCACUCAUGAAAAGGUUUUAUUUACCAGGGACCUCACGGCCACCGAUAAUAGUUUCUGAGUUUCGGAAUGAGAUAUAUGAUGUAAGACACAGAGCUGCUUAUCAUCCAGACUUUCCAACAGUUCUGACAGCUUUAGAAAUAGAUAAUGCGGUUGUGGCAAAUAGCCUAAUUGACAUGAGAGGCAUAGAGACAGUGCUACUAAUCAAAAAUAAUUCUGUAGCUCGUGCAGUAAUGCAGUCCCAAAAGCCACCCAAAAAUUGUAGAGAAGCUUUUACUGCUGAUGGUGAUCAAGUUUUUGCAGGACGUUAUUAUUCAUCUGAAAAUACAAGACCUAAGUUCCUAAGCAGAGAUGUGGAUUCUGAAAUAAGUGACUUGGAGAAUGAGGUUGAAAAUAAGACGGCCCAGAUAUUAAAUCUUCAGCAACAUUUAUCUGCCCUUGAAAAAGAUAUUAAACACAAUGAGGAACUUCUUAAAAGGUGCCAACUACAUUAUAAAGAACUAAAGAUGAAAAUAAGAAAAAAUAUUUCUGAAAUUCGGGAACUUGAGAACAUAGAAGAACACCAGUCUGUAGAUAUUGCAACUUUGGAAGAUGAAGCUCAGGAAAAUAAAAGCAAAAUGAAAAUGGUUGAGGAACAUAUGGAGCAACAAAAAGAAAAUAUGGAGCAUCUUAAAAGUCUGAAAAUAGAAGCAGAAAAUAAGUAUGAUGCAAUUAAAUUCAAAAUUAAUCAACUAUCGGAGCUAGCAGACCCACUUAAGGAUGAAUUAAACCUUGCUGAUUCUGAAGUGGAUAACCAAAAACGAGGGAAACGACAUUAUGAAGAAAAACAAAAAGAACACUUGGAUACCUUAAAUAAAAAGAAACGAGAACUGGAUAUGAAAGAGAAAGAACUAGAGGAGAAAAUGUCACAAGCAAGACAAAUCUGCCCAGAGCGUAUAGAAGUAGAAAAAUCUGCAUCAAUUCUGGACAAAGAAAUUAAUCGAUUAAGGCAGAAGAUACAGGCAGAACAUGCUAGUCAUGGAGAUCGAGAGGAAAUAAUGAGGCAGUACCAAGAAGCAAGAGAGACCUAUCUUGAUCUGGAUAGUAAAGUGAGGACUUUAAAAAAGUUUAUUAAAUUACUGGGAGAAAUCAUGGAGCACAGAUUCAAGACAUAUCAACAAUUUAGAAGUUUCAGGCAGAAGAAUAAACCCAAUCUCUAUUACUACAUAAAUCUGUUCCAGAUGCAGUGUUUGACUUUACGAUGCAAAUUAUACUUUGACAACUUACUAUCUCAGCGGGCCUAUUGUGGAAAAAUGAAUUUUGACCACAAGAAUGAAACUCUAAGUAUAUCAGUUCAGCCUGGAGAAGGAAAUAAAGCUGCUUUCAAUGACAUGAGAGCCUUGUCUGGAGGUGAACGUUCUUUCUCCACAGUGUGUUUUAUUCUUUCCCUGUGGUCCAUCGCAGAAUCUCCUUUCAGAUGCCUGGAUGAAUUUGAUGUCUACAUGGAUAUGGUUAAUAGGAGAAUUGCCAUGGACUUGAUACUGAAGAUGGCAGAUUCCCAGCGUUUUAGACAGUUUAUCUUGCUCACACCUCAAAGCAUGAGUUCACUUCCAUCCAGUAAACUGAUAAGAAUUCUCCGAAUGUCUGAUCCUGAAAGAGGACAAACUACAUUGCCUUUCAGACCUGUGACUCAAGAAGAAGAUGAUGACCAAAGGUGAUUUGUAACUUAACAUGCCUUGUCCUGAUGUUGAAGGAUUUGUGAAGGGAAAAAAAAUUCUGGACUCUUUGAUAUAAUAAAAUGAGACUGGAGGCAUUCUGAAAUGAAAGAAACUCCUUUAUAUAUCCAACCACAAUCAAACAUAUAAAUAAGCCUGGAAAACCAACUACAACCUGCAAUUUAAGAUUACUAUUACUUUAAGAAAAUCAAUUUCAUAGUAUUGGUUUUAAAUCUUUUUAAGUUUUUUUAAUACGAUCUAUUUUUAUAGGUUCUUUUUCAGAAGUAAAAUUUUGUACAUAUAUACAUGUACAUAUCUGUUUAGUUUGGGUUCAUUUCUAUAACAUUUUGUAAGAAAAUAAAAGUUUGAGCACCUGAUUAUAUUUAGUUUUGCUUUUCCAGAUAUUACAUUCUAUAGUUACCAAAAAUGGUUGAAGGGAGGGAUUUCUCAUUGCAGAGGGUGGGGUGCAAGGGAAUAAGACACUUGUACGGAACACUGAAGCUUUGCCAACUUCUACACAUGCCUUUUUUGCAGUCCUUUAACUGUCCACCCUACCAAGAGCUUAUAACCAGUAUCAGAACUGGAUAAUGACGCAGUUUUUCACUCUGACCUCCAUCAUGCUUGCCUGAUUUAAAAGCCCUCAGUUUGCAGUCCAGGGACUGUUCAGGCUUGUCCUCAGCUGAGAGGACACAGGCUAGAGGGACUGUGCAGAACCAGGCUGGGAGAAGGGCUGGGAAAACUGGGAGUGGAGGGUGGAUCCUCAUGGAGCAGGAGAGUAGCUCAUGGCUCCAGGAGCCUGAGGCCAUGCAGUUGAUGGUGAGCUGACAUCAAUUCUAAGACUCAUCCUAAUUGAGGGGUGUUAAAAAGUGUGCUGCUUAGAAUGACCAAAUAUAGUUAUUGUAAAAAAUGAUAUUUAUGAACUUUUUAUUUUAGAAAACAUGAAUUUUAUUGCUCCCUGUAUUAUUUGUUUGAUACUAGGAUUCAUGCUAAACUUUUUAAGAAUGUAUUGGAUAUCAAGAAGCAUUCCUUACAUUAGUAGCAAUAAAUAUUAGAAUAAAUAUGAAAUUGAACUAUUUUCAGAAAAAGGGCAGUAUAUUAAGAGCAGGGACUGUUCUCUAGUUAUUGAGGAAAACUGGACUUUGUUUGUGUUUUUGGUGGAGGAAGAAGUUUAAGAUACUUUAGUCUUAAAUUGAGGUUUGCCAAAUGAGAAGUUCAAAAACUUGGGCUUUCUAAUCAGAAUUUCCAGGAGGAGGAAAGUGUGUGCUGAAUAUUUUAAACAUUUCCCACUGAUCAUACAAAGUCUGAUUUUUAAAUUUACACUUAUAAUGCCUUUGUAUUAAAAUUAUUUUUAACAUGUGCUUUUCCAAAUUAAAAAUGAAGUAGAGUAUACCAAAUGCAUAAACUUUCAUUAGCUAAGGAACUCAUGUCUGAAUUUUGUUGUAGUUUUGAAUGUUGUGCUCUUUCAUACAGAAUGGGAAACAUAAUCCUCAGGUAUCCCAGCAUCUCUUGUUGAAUUGAAGAUUAUUCAUUGCUUUGGCCUCACAAAGUUUUGAUUUCAACUAUCAUAAGUGAAAAUAUCUUCCUUUAAUGUUCUAAGUAGUGAUAAUAUUACUAGAAUGAAAGAAUAAAAAGAAAUUGUUCUUUUAAAAUAUGUGUAACUUCUAAAAAUAAAACUUAAAAUUUAUAUGUA